AGGUGGAGCAAGAUGGCUGUGGAGCUGGGCGUGCUGCUCGUCCGGCCCCGGCCCGGAACCGGGCUGGGUAGAGUGAUGCGGACCCUCCUGCUGGUGCUGUGGCUGGCGACGCGCGGAAGCGCGCUCUACUUUCACAUCGGAGAGACGGAGAAGAAGUGCUUUAUUGAGGAGAUCCCGGACGAGACCAUGGUCAUAGGAAACUACCGGACGCAGCUGUAUGACAAGCAGCGGGAGGAGUACCAGCCGGCCACCCCGGGGCUUGGCAUGUUUGUGGAGGUGAAGGACCCAGAGGACAAGGUCAUCCUGGCCCGGCAGUAUGGCUCCGAGGGCAGGUUCACUUUCACUUCCCAUACCCCUGGUGAGCACCAGAUCUGUCUUCACUCCAAUUCCACCAAGUUCUCCCUCUUUGCUGGAGGCAUGCUGAGAGUUCACCUGGACAUCCAGGUAGGUGAACAUGCCAAUGACUAUGCAGAAAUUGCUGCUAAAGACAAGUUGAGUGAGUUGCAGCUACGAGUGCGACAGCUGGUGGAACAAGUGGAGCAGAUCCAGAAAGAGCAGAACUACCAGCGGUGGCGAGAGGAGCGCUUCCGGCAGACCAGUGAGAGCACCAACCAGCGGGUGCUGUGGUGGUCCAUUCUGCAGACCCUCAUCCUCGUGGCCAUCGGUGUCUGGCAGAUGCGGCACCUCAAGAGCUUCUUUGAAGCCAAGAAGCUUGUGUAGCUGUCCCAGGCGUCACAACCCAUCCUCCCAGGCUGGGGGAGAAAGGACCUCCUGGAACUGACUUCUUCUGUCAGGAGGACUGGUUUCCAGCCAUACCUGUUCUGGAAGGGAGAGGGGCUGGAGGCACCCACAGGCACAAGCUGAAGGCAGCAGCUUGGCUAAUACUGAGCAGGUAGUGGGGCAAAUUCCUGCCCUCUCUCUCUGGCCUCUGGGCCGUUUGGUAGUAAUCACCCAAGGGCUGGUAAAGCCCCUCCUCUUGGCACCUCAGAAUCACAGUGUUACUGAUCAGGGAUGUGAGGCUGCUGUUGGGGGUGGGGGGAGGGGAAUGGGCAGGCAAGCCAGUCUUCUGUCUUCCUUUGCUAACUUAGGGUUUUGAGCAGGUUGGGGUAUGGUGCCUGUCAUACCCACCUGCCACCCUGGGAACCUCACUGUUCUCUCUUUCAGCCUAGACCUGCUGAUCCAGGGUGUGUGUGAGUUGAGGGUGGGUGGAGGGGUUUGCAGUGUGGGAAUGUGGCCCUGCAGUUGACCUGAGCUGCUUCACAUGGUUGUCCAUUCUGGGGCUUAAAGAACUGGGACCAGACCAAGUAGAGGCCUUGGUGCUGGUUGGGGUGGGGCCUGCAGAGUCUUAGUUACUGAUUUCAUUUUCAAUAAAUGUAGGUUUGUUACAUGAGUUUCCCAAUAAAAAAAAAAAUGACUUCUUGUCCAGUGCAAGUGACUCAGUCAUCAGUGGGCACACACUGCAGGGUGCCUCAGGGAAUGCCAGUUCUUCCAAAGAGCAAAGCACUUCACAUUCCAAAGUGAAUUCCCACCAGUCAGCUUCAUUCUUUCCUUCUUCUCCAGGCCUUCCUGUGGCAGGGAAUAGUGGGUUUGUCCAAGAUUAUACAACAAGUAAAUUGGGCUGGGGCUCAAAUUUACACCCUUUCCUCUGUGCCAGCUCCCUGGUGAAGUUCCCUCUUUCUAGAGUCAGUAAGCAGGAUUGUCAUGGAUGCUGCCAGGAAGUGCCUGGUAAGGAGGUGCAUUGAGCAGGGGAGUGCUACAGGACAGCCACCCUGGGCUGGCAGGGACAAGGAUGUUGAUGGGCUAAACCAACAGCAAGUGAUUUCAACCAGGACCAUGAAGGAGAGGAAGGAUUCUGCUGGAAGGAGAUGGCAGGACAGGGGUGGUUGGAGAAGUGGAGGCAAACAGCUGGAAUGGAGGUGGGUGGGUGUUUAAUUUCAGCUGCAGAGGGUGUUGUGAGGAAGCUGGAAAGGAAGGUUGGAUUAGAGAAGCCUCGAGCUCCAGGUAAGCGAUUUGGACAUGCCCACCUUUCAAGAGGGGCUGCAGGCACCCACAGGCACAAGCUGAAGGCAGCAGCUUGGCUGGCUUAAUACUGAGCAGGUGGUGGGGUAAAUGCCUGCCCCCCUCCCUCUGGCCUCUGGGCCCUUUGCAGUAAUCACCCAGGGUCUGGUAAAGCCACUGAGAGCCCUACUGGCACCUCAGAAUCACAGUGUUAUUGAUCAGGGAUGUGAGGCUGCUGUUGGGGGUUGGGGGAGGCAAAUGGGCAGGCAGUUUUGAGAAGAACCUUCUAAUAAGAAAUGUGAGGGAGGUUACAGCAGUGUGUGAGAAAGACCAGGAAGAAGGAGACAAGUUUGGGGGCUGCUUCCCCUAAUGGGAUGAUGCAAUCUGGGCUCAUGCUGCCAACUAAUUCUUCCACAUGAAAAAAAAAAGUUUUUUGGCGGGCACGGUGGUUCACACCUGUAAUCCCAGCACUUUGGGAGGCUGAGGUAGGUGGAUGGCCUGAGGCCAGGAGUUUGAGACCAGCCUGGCCAACAUGGUGAAACCUCAUC